GUAAGUCAACAACAUCCUGGGAUUGGGACACACUUUCUGGGCACUGCUGGCCAGUCCCAAAAUGGAACAUAAGGAAGUGGUUCUUCUACUUCUUUUAUUUCUGAAAUCAGGUCAAGGAGAGCCCCUGGAUGACUAUGUGAAUACCCAGGGGCCUUCACUGUUCAGUGUCACUAAGAAGCAGCUGGGGGCAGGAAGCAGAGAAGAAUGUGCAGCAAAAUGUGAAGAGGACAAAGAAUUCACCUGCAGGGCAUUCCAAUAUCACAGUAAAGAGCAACAAUGUGUGAUAAUGGCUGAAAACAGGAAGUCCUCCAUAAUCAUUAGGAUGAGAGAUGCAGUUUUAUUUGAAAAGUAAAUGUAUCUUUCAGAGUGCAAGACUGGGAAUGGAAAGAACUACAGAGGGACGAUGUCCAAAACAAAAAAUGGCAUCACCUGUCAAAAAUGGAGUUCCACUUCUCCCCGCAAACCUAGGUCAGACUUUUCCUUUCAUCUUUGUGUUCAUCUACUGUAAAGUGUCCGUCUGUGUCUGUGAGGGAUUGGUUCCAGGACCCCUGUGGCUACCAAAAUCCAUGCUUCUCAAGUCCCUUAUGUAAAAUGGUGCAGUAUUUGCAUAUAACCUACAUACCUUCUCUUGUGCAAUCCCUAAUAUAAUGUAAAUGCUAUGUAAUCGUUGUUAUACUGUAUUGUUUUUAUUUGUAUUAUGUUUUAUUGUCAUAUUGUUAUUUUCUCUCAUCUUUUUCAAGUCUUUUCCAUCCACAGUUGGUUGAAUUUGUGGAUGUGGAACCCAUGGAUACAGAGGGCCAACUGUAUUUAGGAUAAUUUCAUCACUUUUAAUUCAAACCAGAAUAUGUGAAUAAGCAGACAGAAAGAAUCUUUUUGAUGUCGAUGUUCAACUAUUUUUGGCACCAUAGUAGAACAUGGUUGCUUUCUAUUUUUUCUUGGGUAUGGAGGUUUCUUGAAGACCUAGAACAUAGAAGAAUGCCUAGUUAAAAAAAAAAAUCAAUGAAACUACGAGUUUUAGGCCAAAUCUGAGAAAAGACCAAAGAUGACUAUGUUUGGGACUGAAGUAAACAUAUCAAGUUAGAACUCUCAUCACAUGUUUGACUCAAAUUGUGGAGCAAAAUAGUAAAUAAAAUAUAAAAAUGAAAAUGAAGAUACGUGAAAUUCAAAUGUCACAACUUGCCUAUUAUUUAUUUUAGUGCAUUUUUUUGUGCUUUUCCCAGUUUGGUGUUAGGUGGCCUUAAGUUCUCAGUAAUGACACUUAUCAAAUAGGAACUUAGUGUUACUCACCUUUAUCCAUUCCCCCAACACUCAACAAAUUGCCUUUGCUAUAUCCCUAUGAGAUGAGCAGAUCAAAUAUUCCCCGUGAGUUAAUGAAAACUGAUUCAACCAAAUGGCGAAGUCAGAGACUAUCGGGGGCCAUGGAGACACUCUGGGCCAUUUUUAUGAGGUAGUCUAGGCUCAUCUUCAUGAGGGAACUGAGGUCUUGGGGGGUGGGGGUUACCCAAAUAGGUUCACAGAAGAACCAGAAAUAAAACCUGCCUUUCUAGACUGUAAGUCUUGUGAUUGUCAUCUAAAUGGUUGUCUCUAUACAGCAACUCAUCUCUAGAACUGAAAAUAAGUUUAAAUCCCUCCUCCAUCCCCAAUAAUUCAAGCUGCAUUUCAGAGAAAACCAGGACUUUGGAAUCAGACAGAUCAACUUUGACUUCUUGAUCUGCUUCUUCAUAGCUAUUUAUGCUUAGGCAAGUUUUGUUUUGUUUUGUUUUACGUUGCCACUCAGUCUUCUCAUCUGUAAAACAGGGAUAAUAACACCUUCCUCAAAUGGUUUUUUUUAUUAGGACUAAAAGAGAGAAUGUGUGGAAAGAUGUUAGUGGAAUUCCUGGCACAUAGUUCACAUGGACAAAAUGGUGUUAACUACGAAAAUUUUUACAGAGAAAAGGGCAACUGACAAAAGCAGGUGUUUGGAAUGAAUUAAGACCAUGGCAGGCUUUUGAGGCCUUUAUAUUUCUCCUGACUGUGCAAUAAAAAUAUUUUGGCUCUCUGUCUAAGACUUGGCUGUCACAGUAGCAAUGGUAAUAUUAGCUACUGUGCCAGAAGCAGCCUAUCAAUAGAGAAAUUGAAAAUCUGACCACACAAAUGCUGCAGCACCCAGCUGAAAUGCAUUUGGAUGACAAUCUCAGAUGGGAAUCGAGAGCAUCUCCUUCUGCCUUGCUAAUAGCAAGCUGAUUUUUAGAAUAUAGUCUAAGUGCUUCUCUUCCAUCCUCCCCAGAUUCUCACCUGCUACACACCCCUCAGAGGGACUGGAGGAAUCCAGACAACGAUGCGCAGGGGCCCUGGUGCUAUACUACUGAUCCAGAACAGAGAGAUGACUACUGCGACAUUCCUGAGUGUGAAGGGCAGGAGUGGCUCUAGAAAAUGUUUUCAUUUCUGCCCUUCACCUGUAAAAUAAUUUGUUGUAAAGCCCCUUCCCACAGGGAUAUUAUUAAUAAUUGCGUAACGUGUUCACCUCUCGGAAAGGAGCAAAACUUUGCUCAGAUCCCAGAAUUAACCUGAUUUUUUUUUUUUUUCUGAGACAGAAUUUUGCUCUCAUUGCCCAGGCUAGAGUGCAAUGGUGCGAUCUCAGCUCACCACAACCUCCGCCUCCGGGUUCAAGCGAUUCUCCUACCUCAGCCUCCCAAGUAGCUGGAAUUACAUGCAUGUGCCACCAUGCCUGGCUAAUUUUACAUUUUUAGUAGAGACAGGGUUUCUCCAUGUUGGUCAGGCUGGUCUUGAACUCUCGACCUCAGGUGAGCCGCCCGCCUCAGCCUCCCAAAGUGCUGGGAUUACAGGCAUGAGCCACCAUGCCCAGCAGACCUGAAUUAUUAUUAUUAAAAUGUUACAUCAACAUGUACAAAUAUAAAACUACAUCUAAACUCUAAGUACAGACUUCUUAUGCUUAAAACUCUUACACAGUGUUAACCCCAAGACAGAUUUGCAAUUAAGUAGUUAAAAUAAGACAACAAAGUCAAUAAAAAUCAAAUAAACAAUAUACAUUUAAUGUGGUAGACUUUGCUGUUUUGCUGAAGCUAAGCAAGGAACCAGUUUUUAAAUCAGCAAUCCGUUAUUUUAAUGGACUGAGCAAUUUAAUAGUGCACCUCAAAGGUCAAUGAUAAAAACUAAAAAAAAAAAAUACCUACUGAAAAAACUGUCAUCGUUUCACAUUUCUGGCUACGUUAGUGCAAAAGGGAAUAAAUAAAGGUGAGAUUUGUGUGA